AUGGACCAUCACAGGCUUGCGGAUGAUCAGCCCAUCUUUGAUCAGCUUCCGGAUCUGCUGACGGGAGUUGGCAUUGGGAGGGCUCGGGGACGGGAAACCCACUCUCAGCCCGCUCCACUUCGCCGAAGAAUUCCAAACCACCCCAGGCUCAGCAGUGUGGAUUGCUCCGCCCAGAGACCGUGGAGGAGGCAGCAGAGAGGUCACAGAGCACAGCAGGCGGGAGAAAACCGCCUCCCGCGAGGUCCAACAGAAACCACGGAGCUCCGGACACUCGGGAUCCCGGGCCGCGGGCGCGCGGCCAGAGCGGCGGGGUGCGAGCGCGGGGGUGCGGACUCACCUCGCGCUUGGGGUGGCCGGGAGCGCGCGCCGCCUCAGUUCCGCGGCUUCCGGCCACAGAGUCCCCGCGCAAAGCGCCGCCGCGUAGCGGGAGGGGCGACCGCGGCAGGCGCUCGGGUUCUUCCUAACCCGAGCCCGCCGCGCUGGCUCCGCCGAGGACGCCAGCAGCUGCAGGCAGCGCUUCAGCUCUCGCCGCCUCGCCAUCGUUGGGGCGAGUCGUCGCCGGGUCACUCCCUUAUUAUGACCUUCGAAUCUGACAGCAGGGCCAGCGGUGGCCUCCUUCAGGCUGCCUCUCCAGCCCUUACCAAGAUGGCCGCCCCUGUGGGCCGGGGCGCCGAAGCCAUCUUGGUAAAGGAAGCGCCUGGGAGCACGCGGCCUGCCCCGGCCCGCCUCGCGACUCAAACACUCUGCAGGGACCCUCCUAAGAUCAAAUUGGUUCCCCCCGCUGUCCUAAGCCAGAGGCUUACUUUCAGAUCGCAUGAACGCAUUCCUGGACACCAGCCACAGUUGCUAAAACUAAAUGGGAUCCUGCAGACCCAUUGACGGACUGUCAUAGCCAACUCAAUCACAGUCGAGAAGCAUUUGAAUACUUACAGCCUAUGGCGCUAGGAUCCUGGUAGCGAAGAAACUAAACUCUAAUUUGAAAUGUUGUACAGUACGUAUUGAAUAUUAAUGGGAGCACGGCAUUGUUCACUGUGUGAUCGUUUACUUUUAAAAUGAUGUCACAGCCCCCUGGUACACACGGUUCUCAUCUAAAUUUGCAUCUUUUUUAACGCUAGGAUAACUAUGAAAGAGCAUACGAUUGUGAUUCUGAGUUUCUUACUGGAUUUGCUUUUUAAACUGCAGAAUGAAAUUAGUUGUUUCAAGAAGUAAAGUACAGGCAUGUCGAAGUAAAAUUCAACAAUGGGUUGUUGGGCAAAAAGAUUAUAAAAGUCCUGGGGUGUGCCAGGGUCAAAAAAAAAAAAAAAAGCUUGUCCCUGGGGUUAUCUUGGCAAAAAAGAAACCACCACCACAGGUUCUAAAUGCAGAUAAGACUGGCAGAAAAAUGCAGACCAAACUAUUCUGCAUUUUGAAAGUGAAUGUGCCUGUGUGACAUUGGAGGAAUGUAAAGAACUGUAUGUCAAGUGUGGACUUUAUCUCCUCAGGCUAGCUUAGAGUGGCUGCUGAACUUAAGGGUGAUUAAGAGCUGCUUGCACCUGGGUGGAGCUGAAACUGCAUAAGGUGAAUAAUACCUUUGUGCAACAGAAGAAAAAAAAAAAAGUAACAGCAUACAUACAAACCCAAAGGGGUCUGUACAGUAAAAGGAAAAGAUAAUGAGGUAACAAGUAAUGCAGAAUGUCUCUCUGAUCACAAGUCAAAAUGUGGAAGUGCGUUUCACACAUCAAAGGUGGGACUUCGUUCCUGGCACUGAUCUCUAUUUGAGCUCCGCUUUUGUAGACUCUACAACAAUUAGGUUAGCUCAUGAAUGCUAAUUUAUCCCACAGGGCACAGUAGAUAUACAGUAAUGGCUAGAAAAUGGUUUGAAACUUUAACCUGGGAUGCCAGAGGUUUGCCUCCCAGACCCCCACUUGUCUCCUCUGCUUGGCCCCAGCUUGGCUGCAGUGCAGGCAACCAGAGCAGGACUCACCCUAUCUCCCCUCUCCCUGGAAGAGAAACAGAAAGAGCGUGAUGAUGAUGGAUGGAGGAAGGGAGAAGUGAAUCAAGGUGCAAGACUGAGAGCUGAUGAAGAGUCAUGAAAUAUCUUGGAGAAAAUUUUCUCAAAUACCCUUUUUUCCUGGAGUUACUCAAGCACAAGAUACAUUUCUGGAGUCAGCCAAGAAACAGGCCCAUGGAAUUUUAAGAGUCAAGAAAACAAAAGAAAUCCAGGCUUAGCCAGCCUAUAGAUUUGUGUAUGGGCAUGAUACAAAGCAUUAAUGAUACAUUUGUUCUUUAUGCCCCAAAAUUAGAAGACUGAUACACCAUCAAGGAAAACCCCCAGAAAAGGGAAAAGCCUUACAAUAGCAAAUAAAAAGAGCCCUACAAAACUAGCCUUUACCAAGUUCUAGGGACUGUCUAAGGAUAUCACAUAUACUACCUUGUUUAAUUCUCACAGGCGCCUACAAGAUGCAUCCUUUCAUUAUCCUCAAUUUGUAGGAGAAAGAACUCAGAGAGGCUGAGGAAACUUGCUCAAGGUUAUAUCACUAGUUAGCGGUGGAGCUGGGGUGUGAACUCAGACCACUGUUCCUAACCCUUGACACUACACUGUCUUGUGAGAUGGACAAUUCAUAAAAGAUAACAACAUGAGUUUUUUUCCCUUAAAACUAAAAAUUGCUUCCUUGAAAAUAAAGAUGCUUAGAGCCGACCCUAAGAAUCACAGCCCAUCCUAAGAAAGUAUGUUCAGUGCAAUUGAGUGUGGCAAAUUAUGGGGAUUAACUUGAAUUCUCUUUAUGUAUUACAAAGUAAGUCAUUAGUAGACUUUGGAACUCUGUUGUUAGUAACAAAUGUCUUACACCCCAGCUCAUUGCAACACCCCAGUGUGCUGUGAUACCACCAUGGCUGGGAACCAUUGGCCUGGAAAAUAGACCUAGGCAGAAAGAUAUUUAUGUAACUGAGUUGAAGAAGGUAGCUGGAAGGUGCAUGAAGCUAGACAUUGGCAGUGUGUGUCAGGUGCUACAGCUUAGGGCCUUCCUGGAAAAUGGGCAGGAAAAAUAGACGGUGACAAAACAAACACAUCAGUAUUAUGGGUAAGCCUGCAGAGAUAAGUUCUGGGGCAUUCUGCUGCCUGCCAAGACUACAUAAGUCCCAGGAGCCACAGCAUUUGUUGCAUAAGAUUAAAUCACUCCAAGCUGAGAAUUUCCCCCUUUAAAGGAAUAAAUGGCAAGCCAUGGGGGAAAGAAUGAGCCAACGCUUCUAGGACAUGUGUGCCUCCACUUAGGCAUUUUGGUCCCUUGACCCUCCAAGACAUUGAUGUGACUUUGGCCAAGUCACUGGUUGUUACCAAGAGGGGAUGAAAUACAUGUUUCCCUAAAUCCCUUCCAACUCAAAAAAUAUGGGAUACUUUGAAUAAAAUGAGAUUGGUACAAAAUUCUGAUUACCUUUGAGAAUGUCUAGCUCUGAUUGCUAGAUUUUCACUGCAUAUUUUCCUCUAGCCUUCAAUUAUCUCCCAAUAAUUUACCCCCAAAUCUUUAUUACUUCAAAUGAAUAGACUUUUCAUAGAGCCCUACUGCAUCUCUAGUCCACAGACACUAAGACAUACAUUAGCAUUAUUAAAUUGUAAGCCAAAGACAUAUCUAUAUAUCUAAAUACUGUGUUUGCAUGCUUUCCCUGAUCAUUAUGUACUUUUUCCCCAUUCCAUUACCACUUAAAAUGCAUUUUGUGAUAUUUCAUUAAAGAGGCAUAAUUACA